GUGUUGGUCCCAGCGGUUCAGCUGAGGUAGGGACGUGCUGUAGGCCGGAAUGUUACCGGCUGUUGGAUCUGUGGAUGAGGAAGAGGAUCCUGCGGAGGAGGAUUGUCCUGAAUUGGUUCCCAUUGAGACGACGCAAAGCGAGGAGGAGGAAAAGUCUGGCCUCGGCGCCAAGAUCCCAGUCACAAUUAUCACCGGGUAUUUAGGUGCUGGGAAGACAACACUUCUGAACUAUAUUUUGACAGAGCAACAUAGUAAAAGAGUAGCGGUCAUUUUAAAUGAAUCUGGGGAAGGAAGUGCGCUGGAGAAAUCCUUAGCUGUCAGCCAAGGUGGAGAGCUCUAUGAAGAGUGGCUGGAACUUAGAAACGGUUGCCUCUGCUGUUCAGUGAAGGACAAUGGCCUUAGAGCUAUUGAGAAUUUGAUGCAAAAGAAGGGGAAAUUUGAUGACAUACUGUUAGAGACCACUGGAUUAGCAGACCCUGGUGCAGUGGCUUCUAUGUUUUGGGUUGAUGCUGAAUUAGGGAGUGAUAUUUACCUUGAUGGUAUCAUAACUAUUGUGGAUUCAAAAUAUGGAUUAAAACAUUUAACAGAAGAGAAACCUGAUGGCCUUAUCAAUGAAGCUACUAGGCAAGUUGCUUUGGCAGAUAUCAUUCUCAUUAAUAAAACAGACUUGGUUCCAGAAGAAGAUGUAAAGAAAUUAAGAACGACAAUUAGAUCCAUAAAUGGACUAGGACAAAUCUUAGAAACACAAAGAUCAAGAGUUGAUCUCUCUAAUGUAUUAGAUCUUCAUGCCUUUGAUAGUCUCUCUGGAAUAAGUUUGCAGAAAAAACUUCAGCAUGUGCCAGGAACACAACCUCACCUUGAUCAGAGUAUUGUUACAAUCACAUUUGAAGUACCAGGAAAUGCAAAGGAAGAACAUCUUAAUAUGUUUAUUCAGAAUCUUCUGUGGGAAAAGAAUGUGAGAAACAAGGACAAUCACUGCAUGGAGGUCAUAAGGCUGAAGGGAUUGGUGUCAAUCAAAGACAAAUCACAACAAGUGAUUGUCCAGGGUGUCCAUGAGCUCUAUGAUCUGGAGGAGACUCCAGUGAGCUGGAAGGAUGACACUGAGAGAACAAAUCGAUUGGUCCUCAUUGGCAGAAAUUUAGAUAAGGAUAUCCUUAAACAGCUGUUUAUAGCUACUGUGACAGAAACAGAAAAGCAGUGGACAACACAUUUCAAAGAAGAUCAAGUUUGUACAUAACACUAGAGGCAUUUCUUAUCAAAAGGAUUGGAUAAUAAAAAUAAGUUUCUACUGGGUAUAUUUCAAGCAUUUAUUUAUUACUUUAGUUACGAAUUCCAAUAUACUUUAAAAUGGUAUUUGUUUUACAGCAUACAUAAAAUGUAGCAAAUCAGUACUGUAAAACAUUUAACAUUCAUACAAUUAUAUAUAAUAUCCUUUUUUUUAAAGAAUGGUAUUUCACAAAAAUAUCUUUUGAAAUUGGCUUUGGAGUUUACAUAUACUGAACAUGAAAGUUUAUAAUAAUGAUGAUACAACUUUCAACAUUGUCAUUUUUUCUUAGAACUUCAGCUGAUUGCAGAGAUAUAAUGAUUACAUUGUUAUUAAAUUUUUUUAACACAAGUAAGUGUCACCAUUUUAUGACAUGAAAUAAAAGGUUAUGACUGUUAUUGAUGUUGAUGUUGACGACCUG